GCGUCGUAGUCUCCUGCAGCGUCUGGGGUUUCCGUUGCAGUCCUCGGAACCAGGACCUCGGCGUGGCCUAGCGAGUUAUGGCGACGAAGGCCGUGUGCGUGCUGAAGGGCGACGGCCCAGUGCAGGGCAUCAUCAAUUUCGAGCAGAAGGAAAGUAAUGGACCAGUGAAGGUGUGGGGAAGCAUUAAAGGACUGACUGAAGGCCUGCAUGGAUUCCAUGUUCAUGAGUUUGGAGAUAAUACAGCAGGCUGUACCAGUGCAGGUCCUCACUUUAAUCCUCUAUCCAGAAAACACGGUGGGCCAAAGGAUGAAGAGAGGCAUGUUGGAGACUUGGGCAAUGUGACUGCUGACAAAGAUGGUGUGGCCGAUGUGUCUAUUGAAGAUUCUGUGAUCUCACUCUCAGGAGACCAUUGCAUCAUUGGCCGCACACUGGUGGUCCAUGAAAAAGCAGAUGACUUGGGCAAAGGUGGAAAUGAAGAAAGUACAAAGACAGGAAACGCUGGAAGUCGUUUGGCUUGUGGUGUAAUUGGGAUCGCCCAAUAAACAUUCCCUUGGAUGUAGUCUGAGGCCCCUUAACUCAUCUGUUAUCCUGCUAGCUGUAGAAAUGUAUCCUGAUAAACAUUAAACACUGUAAUCUUAAAAGUGUAAUUGUGUGACUUUUUCAGAGUUGCUUUAAAGUACCUGUAGUGAGAAACUGAUUUAUGAUCACUUGGAAGAUUUGUAUAGUUUUAUAAAACUCAGUUAAAAUGUCUGUUUCAAUGACCUGUAUUUUGCCAGACUUAAAUCACAGAUGGGUAUUAAACUUGUCAGAAUUUCUUUGUCAUUCAAGCCUGUGAAUAAAAACCCUGUAUGGCACUUAUUAUGAGGCUAUUAAAAGAAUCCAAAUUCAAACUAAA